GUCUUAUUAUCCUCCGGGUCCCUCGCUGGCUAGUAGGAGAGACUGGUGCUUGCCCCGCCCGGUGGACUAACUCGCUUAAUUUUAAAUAAAAAGUCGAGGACACGGCGGUCGUUUUCCCGAAGACAUGGGCCCUCCCAUGGGCCAUUUGCUCCCUGGAGGCCCUCGCGUCUUGCUGAGCCCGGGGAGUUAGGAUGACGCGAGCGAUCUACGCAGACCCCACCAAGAGGCUGGAGCUGUACUUCCGGCCCAAGGACCCAUACUGCCACCCAGUGUGCGCCAACCGCUUCAGUACCAGCAGCCUGCUGCUCCGCAUCAGGAAGAGAACGAGGCGGCAGAAAGGGGUGCUGGGCACUGAGGCCCACUCCGAGGUCACAUUUGACAUGGAGAUCCUUGGCAUCAUCUCCACCAUUUACAAAUUUCAGGGGAUGUCUGACUUCCAGUACUUGGCUGUGCAUACGGAAGCAGGCGGCAAGCAUACGUCAAUGUAUGACAAGGUGCUCAUGCUCCGGCCCGAGAAGGAGGCCUUUUUCCACCAGGAGCUGCCGCUCUACAUCCCCCCACCCAUCUUCUCCCGGCUGGACGCCCCGGUGGACUACUUCUACCGACCAGAGACCCAGCACCGGGAAGGCUACAACAAUCCCCCCAUCUCAGGUGAGAAUCUGAUUGGCCUGAGCAGAGCCCGGCGCCCCCACAAUGCCAUCUUUGUCAACUUUGAGGAUGAGGAGGUGCCCAAGCAGCCACUGGAGGCUGCAGCCCAGACGUGGAGGAGAGUCUGCACUAACCCCGUGGACCGGAAGGUGGAGGAGGAGCUGAGGAAGCUGUUUGACAUCCGUCCCAUCUGGUCCCGAAAUGCUGUCAAGGCCAACAUCAGCGUCCACCCAGACAAGCUCAAGGUCUUGCUUCCCUUCAUAGCCUAUUACAUGAUAACAGGCCCCUGGCGCAGCCUAUGGAUUCGAUUUGGGUAUGACCCCCGAAAAAACCCAGAUGCCAAGAUUUAUCAAGUCCUCGAUUUCCGAAUCCGUUGUGGAAUGAAACACGGUUACGCCCCCAGUGACUUGCCGGUCAAAGCAAAGCGCAGCACCUACAACUACAGCCUCCCCAUCACCGUCAAGAAGACAUCCAGCCAGCUUGUCACCAUGCAUGACCUGAAGCAGGGCCUGGGCCCGUCGGGGACGAGUGGUGCUCGGAAACCAGCUUCCAGCAAGUACAAGCUCAAGGUCAGCCUUCAGACACUGAGGGUGAGAACUCGGGUGCAAAGCCCCAGGGCUGUGUGUGUUGGGGACAUCUGGCGAAGAGGUGGUGACAAGUCUCAGGGAAGUCUGGCACCAGCAGCUGCAUGUGGUUGUCCUUCUCGAGCCCUUUGGGAGCCUGGGCCCCCACUGAGCCACGUGACCACUCCGGGAAUGAUCGGAAUUGGGCACACACAGGAGGACAGAGCCAGAGCAGGCCAUGUGGGCUGCAGCUGUGGCAGGAGCCUCACUGGCUCACGUUUCCGUCAGUGCGGUUGCCCAGCGGGGGUUGGCGGUUUCCAGAGCUGUUCCCACAUUCAGGCUCCCGCAAGCCGCUCCACAGCCCUGGGGGAGGCCGAGAAGGGGGCAUCCCGCACGGUGGAAUCACCUGCUGAGGGAGUGGGUGGCAGAGAUGAGUGCAGCAGAGACGGGUGAUGCGAGGGACUUGCUGUCCCCCAGUGUCUGGGGCCCUGCCUAUUUUCUAGGUUUUUUAGACCUUUGCUGCCUUCCCAGUGAGGGGCGAUCAUGCCACAGCCUGUGCGGCCUUCCUUCUCGAGGCCUCUCCUAGGAGGCCGUUAUCCUUACUCUAGAACUACAUGGCUGGGUACGGAAAGGAGAGAGCAAACACUCACUAAGCCCUGCUUUUCCCAGAAAAGAUGUCAGGGCAGCCCAUAGGGGGACAUAGGGUGACAAAUUAGCAGCAGUGGGUGAGGGAUAAGGUCAGAGUGCAGGAGGGCACAGAGAGCAGAGCCCGGCACAAGGCUAGUGCCAGCCCCAUGCCAUGGGCGCCAUGGCCUGCUGCACGGGCGGGCUCACCGUUUCCAGUGGCCCCAGGAGGGCCUGGGUGCUCCUCUGCCUCUCCCAGAGCCUCCUGGGGAGUUGGACAUUGUUUUUUCCCCAACUCCUCCGUGGCCUUCCAGCCUGUCUGCCCAACCUGCUCCUGGUGACCAGCCAGCUCCCUGGAGAGACCCCAUGGGAGCCUACAUGGAGUCUGCAACACUGGCAGCCCCAGGGCUCUGGCUCACCUUCCCUGUCUCUCUCCCCCUUUGU